AAUCCGUGGUCUGGUACAGGUUUCAGGGCAAAGCGGCCAUGCGUUCCGGGGGCCGCGGGCGACCCCGCCUGCGGCUGGGGGAACGUGGCCUCAUGGAGCCACUCUUGCCGCCGAAGCGCCGCCUGCUACCGCGGGUUCGGCUCUUGCCUCUGUUGCUGGCGCUGGCCGUGGGCUCGGCGUUCUACACCAUUUGGAGCGGCUGGCACCGCAGGACUGAGGAGCUGCCGCUGGGCCGGGAGCUGCGGGUCCCAUUGAUCGGAAGCCUCCCCGAAGCCCGGCUGCGGAGGGUGGUGGGACAACUGGAUCCACAGCGUCUCUGGAGCACUUAUCUGCGCCCCCUGCUGGUUGUGCGAACCCCGGGCAGCCCGGGAAAUCUCCAAGUCAGAAAGUUCCUGGAGGCCACGCUGCGGUCCCUGACAGCAGGUUGGCACGUGGAGCUGGAUCCCUUCACAGCCUCAACACCCCUGGGGCCAGUGGACUUUGGCAAUGUGGUGGCCACACUGGACCCAAGGGCUGCCCGUCACCUCACCCUUGCCUGCCAUUAUGACUCGAAGCUCUUCCCACCCGGAUCGACCCCCUUUGUAGGGGCCACGGAUUCGGCUGUGCCCUGUGCCCUGCUGCUGGAGCUGGCCCAAGCACUUGACCUGGAGCUGAGCAGGGCCAAAAAACAGGCAGCCCCGGUGACCCUGCAACUGCUCUUCUUGGAUGGUGAAGAGGCGCUGAAGGAGUGGGGACCCAAGGACUCCCUUUACGGUUCCCGGCACCUGGCCCAGCUCAUGGAGUCUAUACCUCACAGCCCCGGCCCCACCAGGAUCCAGGCUAUUGAGCUCUUUAUGCUUCUUGAUCUCCUGGGAGCCCCCAAUCCCACCUUCUACAGCCACUUCCCUCGCACGGUCCGCUGGUUCCAUCGGCUGAGGAGCAUUGAGAAGCGUCUGCACCGUUUGAACCUGCUGCAGUCUCAUCCCCAGGAAGUGAUGUACUUCCAACCCGGGGAGCCCUUUGGCUCUGUGGAAGACGACCACAUCCCCUUCCUCCGCAGAGGGGUACCCGUGCUCCAUCUCAUCUCCACGCCCUUCCCUGCUGUCUGGCACACCCCUGCGGACACCGAGGUCAAUCUCCACCCACCCACGGUACACAACUUGUGCCGCAUUCUCGCUGUGUUCCUGGCUGAAUACCUGGGGCUCUAGCGUGCUUGGCCAAUGACUGUGGAGAGGACUGUGAGAGAGAAGGUCCCAGCGGGGGCCAGUGAAGCUCAGGCAGGAUCUGCCUAGGGUGUGCUGGUUUGUCCUUUUCAUACCUUUGUCUCCUAAUUGUGCUACAAUUGGAAGACCUUCUUUCUUUUGAUUGUCUCAAGCUGCCACCCUUCAAGGACAGGGAAGAGACCACUGUGGGAUGACAGCCAGAGGAAUAAGAACUUGCUCCCUCCCCAGAGGUAAACACUUGGUCCAAAGGUUUGCAGGGACCAAAUACUGUUCUUUUUUUUUUUGAGACGGAGUCUCACUGUGUUGCCCAGGCUGGAGUGCAGUGGUGCGAUCUCGGCUCACUGCAAACUCCGCCUCCUGGGUUCACGCCAUUCUCCUGCCUCAGCCUCCCAAGUAGCUGGGACUACAGGUGCCCGCCACCACGCUGGCUAAUUUUUUGUAUUUUUAGUAGAGACGGGGUUUCACCGUGUUAGCCAGGAUGGUCUCGAUCUCCUGACCUUGUAAUCCGCCAGCCUCGGCCUCCCAAAGUGCUGGGAUUACAGGUGUGAGCCACCGCACCUGGCAAAAUGCUGUUCUUUAAGUCAGCGAACUGAAAAAGUAAAAGACUGCUGGGUGUGGUGGCUCACACCUGUAAUCCCAACACUUUGAGAGGCUGAGGGGGAAGGAUCACCCGAGGUCAGGAGUUUGAGACCAGCCUGGUCAACAUGGCGAAACCCUGUCUCUACUAAAAAUACAAUAAUUAGCUGGGCAUGGUGGUGGGCGCCUGUAAUCUCAGCUGCUUGGGAGGCUGAGGCAGGAGAAUCACUUGUACGCAGGAGGCGGAGGUUGCAGUGAGCCAAGAUCACACCACUGCACUCCAGCCUGGGCAACAGAGCGAGACUCCAUCUCAAUAAAUAAAUAAAUAAAUAAAUAUUUUUUAAAAA